UCUGGCCCCCAGCCCUGGUGGGGGUUCCCCUGAGAUAAGGGCUGUUCACUUUCUCUGACCACAUGGUUUCCGCUUCUGUGUCUCUUGUUUCCUAGGCUGAUAAAAAUACUGAGCCCUAGAGGCCCUGGCUUCCUCUGACCCCUUGGGGCAGGCAGCACGCAUCCUGUCCAGCAUGGUGGGGGCAGGGACAGGGGCCAGGGAUUCCCAAGGGGUGACUCAGUGCCUGCCAUGAAACAGUGGGUAGGUGGAAGUGUAUCUCUGCUCUCUAGAGCUGGCACCAGGAGUUGAGUCUCAGUGGAGGAUGCAUUGGGAUUCAAUUGGAGGAACAGGCCUGGAAAAGAAUAAUGAGAUUGAAGAGGGUCAGUUUGAGGACUCAGGUUGGGGCAGGUUUGGAUUAAGUUAGGAAAAGGAUCUGGGAGGGACUCUGUUCAGUGUAGGUCAACUGAGCAUUAUGUAGCCCAAAGAUAAAUUUAAACCCUGCUUCAAGCUUACAAUCUAGUGGGGAGGCAGACCCAUACCUAGUUAACUGAUUCAAGGCAUGAUGAGUAAACUUUAAGAUGAUUACAGAAAGAGGGGAGAUUAAGUCCAUUUGAAAGCAUCCAGGGAGCCUCUGAGGAGACAGCAUUUGAACUUGCUCUAAUGAAUGGGUUCACUAGGUGGAGGUGGAUGGAAAGGUUCCAUAGGCGAAUAACACGUCUUGAGCGAGCCUGACAAGUCAGAAAAUGCAGUAUGUUCUGGGAAAGGAGCGUCCUGAGGGAGAAGAAGCACAGGUGUGAGGGAACAUGUGAUGAAGAAAGGACCACAGAAAGUCAAGGUCAGAGAUUGGACUGCAUCCUGUGGGCAGUGGUCCAGGUGACGAUGAAAAAGAGGGAGAACAGAAAACUUUGGAAGGUGUCUGCCACAUUGAUCCUGGAAUGUGUGUUUAUUUGGGGUUAUAUAAAUCUGUUCUGUGGAAGCCACCUGAAGUCAGGAAGAGAUGGAGGGCAUCCUUCAGGAGUGAGAUGAGACCUCAUCAUACUUGACUGUCCAGCAUCAUCUCUGAGCCUCAGCCUUUCCUGCCUUUGACUGAAACAGCAGUAUCUUCUAAGCCCUGGGGGCUUCCCCGGGCCCCAGCCCCGACCUAGAACCCGCCCGCUGCCUGCCACGCUGCCACUGCCGCUUCCUCUAUAAAGGGACCUGAGCGUCCGGGCCCAGGGGCUCCGCACAGCAGGUGAGGCUCUCCUGCCCCAUCUCCUUGGGCUGCCCGUGCUUCGUGCUUUGGACUACCGCCCCGCAGUGUCCUGCCCUCUGCCUGGGCCUCGGUCCCUCCUGCACCUGCUGCCUGGAUCCCCGGCCUGCCUGGGCCUGGGCCUUGGUUCUCCCCAUGACACCACCUGAACGUCUCUUCCUCCCAAGGGUGCGUGGCACCACCCUACACCUCCUCCUUCUGGGGCUGCUGCUGGUUCUGCUGCCUGGGGCCCAGGGGCUCCCUGGUGUUGGCCUCACACCUUCAGCUGCCCAGACUGCCCGUCAGCACCCCAAGAUGCAUCUUGCCCACAGCACCCUCAAACCUGCUGCUCACCUCAUUGGAGACCCCAGCAAGCAGAACUCACUGCUCUGGAGAGCAAACACGGACCGUGCCUUCCUCCAGGAUGGUUUCUCCUUGAGCAACAAUUCUCUCCUGGUCCCCACCAGUGGCAUCUACUUCGUCUACUCCCAGGUGGUCUUCUCUGGGAAAGCCUACUCUCCCAAGGCCACCUCCUCCCCACUCUACCUGGCCCAUGAGGUCCAGCUCUUCUCCUCCCAGUACCCCUUCCAUGUGCCUCUCCUCAGCUCCCAGAAGAUGGUGUAUCCAGGGCUGCAGGAACCCUGGCUGCACUCGAUGUACCACGGGGCUGCGUUCCAGCUCACCCAGGGAGACCAGCUAUCCACCCACACAGAUGGCAUCCCCCACCUAGUCCUCAGCCCUAGUACUGUCUUCUUUGGAGCCUUCGCUCUGUAGAACUUGGAAAAAUCCAGAAAGAAAAAAUAAUUGAUUUCAAGACCUUCUCCCCAUUCUGCCUCCAUUCUGACCAUUUCAGGGGUCGUCACCACCUCUCCUUUGGCCAUUCCAACAGCUCAAGUCUUCCCUGAUCAAGUCACCGGAGCUUUCAAAGAAGGAAUUCUAGGCAUCCCAGGGGACCACACCUCCCUGAACCAUCCCUGAUGUCUGUCUGGCUGAGGAUUUCAAGCCUGCCUAGGAAUUCCCAGCCCAAAGCUGUUGGUCUGUCCCACCAGCUAGGUGGGGCCUAGAUCCACACACAGAGGAAGAGCAGGCACAUGGAGGAGCUUGGGGGAUGACUAGAGGCAGGGAGGGGACUAUUUAUGAAGGCAAAAAAAUUAAAUUAUUUAUUUAUGGAGGAUGGAGAGAGGGGAAUAAUAGAAGAACAUCCAAGGAGAAACAGAGACAGGCCCAAGAGAUGAAGAGUGAGAGGGCAUGCGCACAAGGCUGACCAAGAGAGAAAGAAGUAGGCAUGAGGGAUCACAGGGCCCCAGAAGGCAGGGAAAGGCUCUGAAAGCCAGCUGCCGACCAGAGCCCCACACGGAGGCAUCUGCACCCUCGAUGAAGCCCAAUAAACCUCUUUUCUCUGAAA